AGAGCUGGCGCUCUAGCCCACGGAGUUGGUUAACUCCUCUCACCGGCCCCUGGAAAGGGUUCCAAGUCCUUUAGUACCCGACGCUCUUCCUCGCCGGUCCACCUACCCAGACAAGGCAAACGGAAAUCUGCAGCAGGACUCAGCUUGGUGCACACAACUCCGCCCUCGCCACACCCACUCUGCAGCGUCUGGCCCGGCAAUACCCAUCUGGGCGCCCCUCCUGCUUCCUCUAGGCUGUGAGUACGCGUGCUGCCCCAGACUCUCCCUCCUCCACCCACACCCGCAGUGACACCCCUUCCGCCAAAUUUGUUUCUCUUUCUUUCAGCGCCUGCGCGCUGUCACGUUACGGCGGAACUAAUCCAGCGACGCCUGCGCUUUGACGCAUUUGGUGCCGUGGAAGGGAAAAAGGGGGACUGCAGUAUGCGUCACACCCGGAAGCGGCGAGCCGGAAGUGGGGUUAGCCAGGUUAUCCCCAGGGGUGGAGAAGCGGAGGCCCAGGAGGAGGGGGAAUAAAGAAGGUGGAGGAUCCUGGCUACCACUCUGAAUCCGAUACCGCUUCUCUUAGACCUCAGCGACAGAAAAAGGGAAGGGUGUCUCAUCCCCCUUCCUCCUCUCCUCCCUGUCCUGAGCCUUAGCCAUGGCCGAGGCAGGGGCUGGGCUGAGCGAGACCGUCACUGAGACAACGGUUACCGUGACAACCGAGCCCGAGAACCGGAGCCUUACCAUCAAACUUCGGAAACGGAAGCCAGAGAAAAAGGUAGAAUGGACAAGUGACACUGUGGACAAUGAACACAUGGGCCGCCGCUCAUCCAAAUGCUGCUGUAUUUAUGAGAAACCUCGGGCCUUUGGCGAGAGCUCCACGGAAAGUGAUGAGGAGGAAGAAGAGGGCUGUGGUCAUACACACUGUGUACGUGGCCACCGCAAAGGACGGCGUCGUGCAACCCUAGGACCGACCCCCACCACCCCUCCCCAGCCUCCUGACCCUUCCCAGCCCCCUCCAGGGCCAAUGCAGCACUAAAUCCCUCUCUCCUCCAGCAUUCCUGUGUCUGUCUGGCCCUAAAUGUAUCCAUGUGGCUACUUCUCCAGCCCCCUCCUUCCCUCUCUUCUGCCUGAUAGAGGGAAGAGGAAGAGGAGGACGAACAGAGAUCCUGAAAUUCUGACUUGCUGCUAUUCCAGAACCCAGCCUCCUGGGUUUCCCCAGUCCUCAUUUUUCCUCCCAAUACCCACCCUUCUCUCUCGAGGGAUCUAGGCACCUUGGUCCCAGUGUCUUCCUUUUGUUCUCACUGCCAAACUGCCUGUCCUGGGAUCUAGUUAUCUUGGCCCUGCACUCUCAACAUGAGUAGCGAACACUUAAAUUGGGUUUUCAACAGUCCCAGCUUUCACUGCCAGGGUCCCAGUCAGAUUCCAGGAAUUUGCGCCCUAACUUUGCUUGCUAAUCCUGGUUUAGAGCUAUCCCACUAAAAUAUUUAAUCCUAAUUCUUAGUCCUUGCCUGUGAGAUAUGAGGUCUUACAGGAGACCUCAGAGCUCCCAGCCCUUCUCCUCCUGCUAACCCUUCUCACACCCUCAAGAGGAGUUAGAAAAGAGGUCCUUGUCAUUCUCACCUCUUAUGGAAAAUGGAAUAAGAAAUAAUCAUAUCCUUUCUUCCCACCCUUCUCCUGUUAUUUAGGAUUUCUGACAAAGCUGGCUUGAGAUUGGUCACUUAGAGCCGACUGUCUCCUCUGCCUUUUGUUUUUCAGCUUCAGAGACAGAUCCAAUAUAGUCCCAGGGACCUGGGUCUCUGGGAGAGGAAGGAAGAGGGAGGGAGCAAAGAGAUUGGGGUAUGUCCCCUGUAGUACACUCUUACCUCUUACUUCCUAGACUUUGAUUUCUCCGGCAGCCCAGAUGUUCAGUUCUCUUGGCCCCUCUCUACCCCUUACUGGGAUCCGGUUUUCAUUUUCCGGUCCUUUUGCCAUACACAGUUACAGAGAUCAGUCAAAUCCAUACCACCACUGAGAUCUCAUUUAUUGCCACAGAUGCACAAAAUAAAUAACCCAAAAUCACAAAA